ACGCUAGGAGCUACCACAACAGGUGAUUCCCUUCACCAAGUCUGGGUCUAGACUUGGCCCCCGCGAGUUCACGUCCCUGCCUAAUGCGCCUGGAGUCCGGGUGAUGGCCCUGGAUCCGCUCCCGGCCCCAAGCUCCACACAGCCGGGAAGGAAGCUCGCGUUUGUUUUGCUGGCGCCAGGGAUACGGUCCAGGCCCCGCCCCGCCCCGCGCUGAUCCCAGGGUAGUGGGAAAGUGCGCUCCCCAAGAAUUUGCGGUGCAGGGGCCGCGGCCACCGCCUUCUGUCCGCAGGUGCUGCGAGCCGUAAGCGCCCCCCACCCGCGCUAUGGGCUCGGACGCCUGGGUGGGCCUUUGGCGGCCACACCGGCCCCGCGGCCCCAUCGCGGCGCACUACGGAGGCCCCGGGCCCAAAUACAAGCUGCCGCCCAACACCGGCUACGCCCUGCAUGACCCGUCGCGGCCGCGCGCCCCCGCCUUCACCUUCGGCGCGCGCUUCCCCACGCAGCAGACGACGUGCGGCCCCGGGCCAGGCCACCUGGUGCCCGCUCGCAUGACCGUGCGCGGCACCGACGGCGCCCCCGCCUACUCCAUCUACGGCCGCCCACGCCGCUCAGCGCCCUUCCUCACUCCGGGACCUGGCAGGUACUUCCCGGAGCGAGCGGGGAACGCGACGUACCCCAGUGCGCCUCGGCACACCAUUGCUCCCCGAAACUGGGGUGUCCAGGCGGAACAGCAGAGCCCAGGUCCCGCGGCCUAUACGGUGCCCUCGCUCUUGGGUCCGCGCGUCAUCGGCAAAGUCUCCGCCCCAACUUGCUCCAUCUACGGCCGCAGAGCGGCUGGCAGUUUCUUCGAGGACCUCAGCAAGGUGGGGGAGGGGCCGGGGCGGACGCAGGGGGUCCCUGGUCCGCGGCAGUGGAGGCGGCAGCCAGCACCCUCUGCCCUCUCGCAGACCCCGGGCCCCUGCGCCUAUCAGGUCGUGAGUCCAGGGGUCUACAAGUCCCGGGCCCCCCAGUUCACGAUUCUGGCGCGGACUUCGCUCCCCCAAGACAACACUCGGAAGCCAGGGCCCGCGGCCUACAACGUGGAUCAGGUGGCCUGGAGCCCAGGGUCAAGGGUCAGAGUCAGGAGAGUGGGGAGGGCCUGAGGUCGGAGUGAUGGGAUCAGAGUCCCCGGGGGUCCAGGGGUCCCGGCGCGGAGAGGAUGCCGGCCCCGCGAGGUCAGCGGUGUCUCCGGGCCCGCAGCACCGGAAGCCCCGCGGCUGGAGUUUCGGGAUCCGGCACUCGGACUACCUGGCCCCGCUGGUGACCGACGCGGACAACUGACCCGCCAGGCGGGAGCGGCCCCACACGUGUUUGCUUAAAGUCUGCGAGUCCGCA